AGCCCCCGCCGCCCGGGGCCGCGCGCCCACGCGCUUCCUUCCGCCCUCCGCGCCGGGGUGCAGCCCUCUGUCCUCCGGGGCCCCCGAGGGCGCCAGGGCCGUUAGGGUCCCGGGCAGCGCUCCCGCGCCCUGUCCCGUGUGAGUCCCUGUGAAGACCCCCGAGCUUGAGGGUGCGGGGUGGGCCGGUGGCCUUCCUCUCCUGAUUCUCCCGGAAUCUCCAAACUUCAGAACUGCUGUCCAGCUCAGUGUCUUACGCGUGAGGAUACUGAGGUCCAGGACCAGAAGGGACAGUGGCAGUGCCAAGGGCUGGCUUGGAGGGCUUUCCACUUCCAUCCGACCCCUUCCUCCGGAUGAGCAUAAACUCUAAAUGAAAUCUCCAUCAUGCCCCCCGUGUAAACGCAGCCUCAGAACAAGCCUUUACCUCGCACCCCCACCUCUAUCACAUUGCCACACCCACGUCUUUUCUAUGUAAAAAGCCUAUAGUUGACUUCUCCAAAGCCGUCCAUUGAGUUUGAGGCAGAACGGGGUUACAGCCUCUCCUUCACAGGGGCUGCUUCUUAGGCUGAGGAUAGUUAGGUGGUGGGGAGGGAAGCUAUGUGGCCCACUUUUGGGGUCCAGAUACUUGAGGUGAAAUUCACUGGAUGCCAGAUUGACUGUCAACGUCAUCGCCCUGUACGAUCUGUCUAUAAAUCCCCCGCCUCUGGUGGCGUGGUUGUCCGGGAAGGUCAGGCAGUCUUCCCUGUUCACCAGCCUUGUUUGCAAAGGCUGAGCUCCAAGGGUCACCACUGUUGACAUCAAAGUCCAAGAGGGCAGUACACCCAGCUAAGGACCUCUUACCUGUAGGGAAGGAAUGUGCAUUGCCAUAGACCCUGUUAGUCCAAAUAGUUGACUCCCCUCCCCUGGAUGGGAGUGGAGGAGUUGGUUUGCUCAGUGUCUUGGCACCGUCUGGGGCAAGCAUUUUCCUUCACCUGGAGGAAAGCAGUGGAGUCCAGUCCUUAGGUUCUGAUAAGGAAGCCUAUAGACUAAACGGAGUUGGGUUUUUAAAAUGGUGUGGUUAUUUACACAUUUAUGUUUUAAAUUGCAGUUUGAGAGCAUGAUUUCUACCGAAGCAAGGGGACAUCCCAAGCUAAAUUCAAAGGACUGAGCCUUUUCAAAAUUCUAGGAAACCGAUGAGUUUUUCUUGCUUAACCAUAGCGUUUAUACGUAUAAGUGUAUUUUCUAUCUCAAUUUUUUUGAGAAAAAAUAUUAAAUUUUGAAAAAAAAGUAUUUGGCCUUUCCAGAUUUUUUGUUUGUUUUUUGAGACGGAGUCUCGCUUUGUCGCCCAGGCUGGAGUGCAGUGGCGCGAUCUCCGCUCACUGCAACCUCCGCCUCUGUGGUUAAAGUGAUUCUCCUGCCUCAGCCUCCCGAGUAGCUGGGACUACAGACUCGUGCCACCACGCCCGGCUAAUUUUUUGUAUUUUUAGUAGAGACGGGGUUUCACCGUAUUAGCCAGGAUGGUCUCAUCUCCUGACCUCGUGAUCCACCCGCCUGGGCCUCCCAAAGUGCUGGGAUUACAGGCGUGAGCCACCGCUCCCGGCCAUGGUCUUUCCAGAUUUUAAGAAAUGAAUGAAUUAUUUGGCUCACUUAACUAGAGGGGACUUUAUACCUAUAAAUGUAUUUUCUUUCUUAGUUUUUUUUUUGGGGGGGGGGAUAAACUUCAUUUAAUUGUGGUCUUUUUUUUGUUGUCAGCCUACAUCAUGCUUUGAUGUUUUUUCUUUUUAAAUCAACAUCAUUAAAGUUUGAAAAAUAUCAUAAAAUCCCACCAGCUAUUUUAAAUUUAUUUUUGCCACUAGUUCCUACCCAUAUGUCUAUGCAUGUUUUACAUAGUUGCAAUCAUAGUAUGUGUACAUAUUUUGGAUCUUAAUUUGUGCUUUUCCACUAGUGCUCUUGGUAUUACAAGAAGGGAGAGAGCACUUCCAAUAAGUGCCUUUAUUCCUGCUCACAGACUGUUUCUCAGAUUACCUUUUAUCAGGUGGACUGAAGUUGAAAACAGUUUAACGGGGAAUUGUGAUAACACUUUCAUUUGAGAAUAUGACGGUUUGGAGAGUGAGUUGAUGACAUUUUAAUGUUUUUCUUAAUGAACCUUAAAAGCGCUUCUGGAGAACCUUAAGAAUCCCUUCCCAGCAAAGUGAGGUGGUGGUUGAUUUAACUUGCUGGUCUUUGUGGUAUCAUGUGUGCUGUUGGCCUUUAUUUCAGGAUGAAGGCUGCCGAUGAGUGUUUUGGUUUGGUUAUGCAUUGGUUUGGUUAUGCGUAAGUUAAGGUCAGGUUGCUUUGAGACAGAUGUGUUAUUGGAAAGAGGGUUUUAGAAGUAUUGAGGAGGUGGGGAUGGCAUUAGGGAAGGGUUGUGCCCUGAGCUGGGUAGGCCCGUUGGUUGGUAAACCUUUGUUGUCUUUGAGGAGGCCAAAGAAGCCUUGCAUGGACGCCUCACACUUGCCACUUACAAACAGUGGAAAACUUAAUUUUUUGUACUCUCCUUCCUUUAACUCCUCUCAGGCUUUGCUUUUUUUUAAAUAUUUUUUAAAAAAAUUUAUUUUUAAUUUUUGAGGAUACACAGUAGGUGUAUAUAUUUAUAGGGUACAUGAGAUAUUUUGGCACAGGCAUGCAAUUUGUAAUAAUCACAUCAUGGAAAAUUGGGUAUCCAACCCCUCAAGCAUUUUUCUUUUGUGUUACAAACAAUCCAAUUAUACUUUUAGUUAUUUUAAAAUGUACAGUUAAAUUAUUAUUGACUGUAGUCCUCCUGUUAUGCUAUCGAAUACUAGGCCUUGAGGAAAGUUUAAAACCAGAGUAUUGUCAUGCUGGCUUUGAAACAGGAGGGUACUUCACAUCCCCAAACUAAAUAAUCUGUAAUAAAAAUUUUUCAUAUUUUUUGUUUGUUUGUUUAAUUGACAGGGUAUUGUUCUGUCACCCAGGCUGGAGUGCAGUGGCAUAAUCAUUGCUCACUGCAGCCUUGAACUCCUGGGCUCAAGCAGUCCUCCUGCCUCAGCCUCCCGAAUAGCUGGGACUAGAGGUGUGCCCCACCAUGCUCGGCUAAUUUUUUUUUUUUUUAAUUUUUCUGUAGAAGUGGGGUCUUACUUUGUUGCCCAGGAUGGUCUCAAACCCCUGGCCUCAAGCAGUCUUCCCGCCUUGGCCUCCCAAAGUGCUGAGAUUAUAGGUGUGAGCCACCAAGCCCAGCCAAAAAUCUUUCAGAUUUUAAAAAAUCAAAUGUAUUCUAAUGACUCAUUUAACAAGAGUGAAUUUGCCAUUAGAGUAUUAUAUAAAAAGUACACAUAGAAAAUUUCGGUGCUAAACACUCUUACCGUUUCUCUGUAGUCAUAUAUGCUCCAAACUUAUCUUGCCUCAAGUACAUGUGACUUGUUCUUGGGGAGGUAUCAGGUAAGGAGUUAACAUGAAGUGAAUAAAACCUGAACACUCUAAAAAGAGCAGAUCUGUCUAAGAUAACUAUGCAAAGUCAGUUCUCACAUCCUUAAUUUGGGUUGGAGGAUCCAAAUUUAAAGUUUCUUUGAGUAAAUGUGGAUAUUAUAUUUUUGUAAUCCUGUGAAUGGUUAACUGUAGUUCUGGCUUUUGGGCAUGUGACCAUUCUCAAUUUCUUCUCAACUGUAUUGCUAUUAAAACAACAAAACAAAUCUCAAAUUAAGCCAAACAAAUAUUGGCCCCUCAAAUGCUUAGGUACUACUAGCUCAAGAUGGCCUCCUCUGCAUUCCUCUUUCUUUGGAAAGUCCUGCCCUCUUUCAGAGUCAGGCUCCUCUUGUUUCCGUGACACCAUCUAACUGUUUGAAGAUGAUUUUCCUUUAUUUGCUCAGUUCUUCUUUUGAUUCCUUUCCUUUGAGCUGCGAUUCUACAUUUUAACCUUAUUUGAGGAUUGAGUACUGUUGUGUAUUCACCUGCAUUUCCCUUUGUCUUGUCUCUCCAGAUUAUCAAUCCCUUGAACGCAGGGACUGUUUCUUAUGUUAUCUCUGUGCCUACACCACACCAGGUAGAUUUCUGAACAGCUGUUACAGUUCAAAUCUGAACAUCAAUGAUGUACUAGGGAACUACUCAUUGACUCUUGUUGAUGCAUUGGAUACACUUGCAAUAAUGGGAAAUUCAUCCGAGUUCCAGAAAGCCGUCAAGUUAGUGAUCAACACAGUUUCAUUUGACAAAGAUUCCACCGUCCAAGUCUUUGAGGCCACGAUAAGGGUCCUGGGAAGCCUCCUUUCUGCUCACAGAAUAAUAACUGACUCCAAGCAGCCCUUUGGUGACAUGACAAUUAAGGACUAUGAUAAUGAGUUGUUAUACAUGGCCCAUGACCUGGCGGUGCGGCUCCUCCCUGCUUUUGAAAACACCAAGACAGGGAUUCCAUAUCCUCGGGUGAAUCUAAAGACAGGAGUUCCUCCUGACACCAAUAAUGAGACAUGCACAGCGGGAGCCGGUUCCCUCCUGGUGGAAUUUGGGAUUCUGAGUCGACUCCUGGGGGACUCCACAUUUGAGUGGGUGGCCAGACGAGCAGUGAAAGCCCUUUGGAACCUCCGGAGCAAUGAUACAGGAUUACUAGGCAAUGUCGUGAACAUUCAGACGGGCCACUGGGUUGGAAAGCAGAGUGGCCUGGGUGCCGGGCUGGACUCCUUCUAUGAAUACCUCUUGAAAUCUUACAUUCUCUUUGGAGAAAAAGAAGACCUAGAAAUGUUUAAUGCUGCAUAUCAGAGUAUUCAGAACUACUUAAGAAGAGGGCGGGAAGCCUGCAAUGAAGGAGAAGGAGACCCUCCACUCUAUGUCAACGUGAACAUGUUCAGUGGGCAGCUGAUGAACACCUGGAUUGACUCUCUGCAGGCCUUUUUCCCUGGACUGCAGGUGCUGAUAGGAGAUGUGGAAGAUGCCAUCUGCCUUCAUGCCUUCUACUAUGCCAUAUGGAAACGAUAUGGUGCCCUCCCUGAGAGAUAUAACUGGCAGCUGCAGGCCCCUGACGUUCUCUUCUACCCACUGAGACCAGAGUUAGUGGAAUCCACAUAUCUCCUCUACCAGGCAACCAAGAAUCCCUUCUACCUCCAUGUAGGAAUGGAUAUUCUGCAGAGUCUGGAAAAGUACACAAAAGUCAAGUGUGGGUACGCCACGCUGCAUCACGUCAUUGACAAGUCCACAGAAGACCGGAUGGAGAGCUUCUUUCUCAGUGAGACCUGUAAAUAUUUGUAUCUGCUGUUUGAUGAAGACAAUCCAGUACACAAGUCUGGAACCAGAUACAUGUUCACAACAGAGGGACACAUUGUAUCUGUGGAUGAGCAUCUUCGGGAAUUGCCAUGGAAGGAAUUCUUCUCUGAAGAGGGAGGGCAGGACCAAGGGGGAAAGUCUGUGCACAGGCCGAAACCUCAUGAGUUAAAAGUCAUCAACUCCAGCUCCAACUGCAAUCGUGUACCUGAUGAGAGGAGGUACUCCCUGCCCUUAAAGAGCAUCUACAUGCGACAGAUUGACCAGAUGGUUGGUUUGAUUUGAUCUGCUCUCUGUGAGGCCUCAUCUUGAACCAGACCUUAACGACCAAACCCAGACCAUGCCAAAGUCCAGUCUGAAAUGAAAGGGGACAGAAGUCUUGCUGUCCAUGGUGGUGUAGGAAUUUCUGUGCAACACCUCACCACGUCUGGUUAAUCCUUGCACACUUCAGUGUUUCUCUCCUGUUCAAUAAAAUGCCCUGUUAAGGAUAUAAUUUGAAGUGAGAAGAUACAUGGAAAUUGCCCUCUUAUGACAUGUUGAUGUUAUAAGCACAAUAGAUGGGGCAUCUUUGGAUUGAUGUUCACAGCUUUAUACUUCAGAACCUAAGUCUCUUCACUUUGCUGGCACCUGCUAUACUGGAGUAUUGCUAUGUCUUUAAAAAAUUUUUUUUAUUAUAUUUUAUUUUUUUGAGACAGGGUCUUGAUAUUUUUUUGGGACAGGGUUACCUGGGCUCAAGUGAUCCUUCUGCCUCAGCCUCCCGAGUAGCUGGGAUUACAGGUGAGCACCACUGUACCUGGCUAGCUACUUCUUUGUUAGAGGAUUGAGAAUGAAAUUUCUGCAAAAGGGCCCAUGGUUCAUUUGGUAUCCCUAUUUAAUUGCAUUGAAAAUGUCAUCCUUUCUGUUGUUAGAUAAUUGGGGUCUUCCCCUGAUAUCCAACCGUGAUUUUGGAUCACAUGGGAGAAAAAGUCAUCCAGUUUUUCAUGUUUGCCUCAAGUAAUCUUUACAGUGUUACAAAUUAUUUGCUUAAGAAGAAUGGUCUUAACCAGAAUUCUUAACAGAUAGUCUCUUAGGUUAUUAUGUUAUGGUCUAAGAGGUUAACUGACAUCUUUUGGGUGGUAUUUUGCAUUUUGAAUAUGAACUUACCUGAGGAACUCCCAUAGUUCCAGAAUCAGGUGCCUUUUAGGGAGAGAACAAUACCUAAGAUUGUCUGAGCUUCCAUCUUUCUCAUAUUUCCUAAGCAAGGAUUCUCACUUCUGACCAUAUUUGGGUUAGAGUUCUGUUUUGUUUCUGUUUUCUGUGUCUAGUGCCAAUUAGCUAAAUCAGGGAGAAAGAAAUGAUCACAUGACUUUUAGCAUCCUUGAGCCAUUUCUCUGUGUAAUACAGGCUUUAGAUUAGUGCCUUAUAUUGGUUUUGGUUUGGGGCACUGGAUGUCGCAGCUACUGCUAUGGUUUCAGGAGGCCUGUUUAGCCACAUGGUGAGACCGUGGUGAAAGGGGGAUGGAAAUUGCUUGGCCAGUCUUUGCCUUUCAUCCUGUAAAAGUAAGCAUGUAGAAGGAGGAAGUUGUGCUAAAAUGCCUUUGUUUUUUUGUUAUUAUUUUCUUAGCCAGAACAUCUCUCUUUGAACUCACACUGAUACACACCUGCUACUCUUACACAGUGCAGCAGGGUUGACUCUUAGUCUGGCUUCCAUGAAGCGUCAUGGGUGGAAACGCAUUCUAGUAAAAAAGGUAGGAAAUCCCUAAAACUUCCAGCCUCACAUAGCACGGUUCUCACCUGUCACUGUUUUCCCACCUCUAAGGAUUUCAUGUACAUCUUUUCAAAGCUAGAAAUAAGCACUGUCUAAGUUUAUGUUGCAUUUUUAGUCAAAAGGGAGAAAUCUUAUUCCUUCUUGAAAAUUUUAAGUGUUAUGGUUUUAUAUAGUUCAGUUCUUUGAGAUUUUUGAAAAGAGUAUUUUCAGUAAUAAACGUGCCAUCUCUAUCUCUUAAACAUUUAUUACAACAAUUGUUUUAAAAUAGAAAAAAUAAAAUGCUUCUAUUUUACCUUUUUUCAUUUCAGAAGCAUUAUUCUGUUUAUUAACAGUGUCCCAUCUACUGAAUAGAAAACUUUGAGAAUAAUAUAUAUAUAUAUUUUAAAUGUUUUCACUGACUCAUUGAAAAUGUUAAUUACACACACAUGCAUGCAUGCACACACGAGCAUACUUGUACCUUUGUCUCUGGGCAAACAGGUGGGACUGUUAGUGACCCAUUUGGGAAAAUAGAGCAUCUCAGAGAAGGAGGUGAGUUCUUCCUGCCUGUGAUUUCUCUUGGCGCUCCCCUCCUCUCCCGCUCUGGCUUCUGUGGCGGCAGUGGUGGGUAAGCACUCCAGUGUUCUCUUAAUGAGGCACUUUGCCUGUCACUCGAGCAAGCCUGGGUGUUCCUUCCUCCUCAUGCUCCUGGAAUAGGGAAUAGGGAUCUCAUGCUUGCAAACUACACAAUGCUGCAGGUGCUUCCCAGGGGCCACAGGCUGUCAGGAAACGUGUUUUAUGUUAAGUCACAAACCCACUUGACUUCUGGGUACUGGAAUUAAUACCAGUGGGUGAGACUGAGGGUGAGUGAGUUAGUACAUAUUAAUCCUGGUUGUUGAGCUUCCAGACUACCCCGUCCAAAGUUUGAUGCUAUGUAGUCAGUGGUUUGUGGGGCUGGAUGCCAGAAGGUUCUUUGAGCCAGUUUCAAAGGUUACUUGUUUUUUUUUUUUUUUUUUAAAGUCAGAAUGUUAACAGCUGUGAUAUAUCCUGCAGGGCUUUUGCAGUUUCUUCUGUUCUGUGUUCUGAAAUACUGGGUAGAGAAUGGCUGAGGAGGAGAUUACCAGAGAAGUUGCUUUGCUCAGUGCUUUGCCCCAGGAUUGCCUCAAAUCUGAGUGGACUUCAUCCUUUGCGGCGGCUCUGAGCCUGGCCCAUCUUCCUAUUCCCACGUGUAGCUAGUGUCUAGUGUCAGCUUUGCUCAGUGUGGUGGAAACAUUUUGCAGAACUGUUGUAGAAAGCUGCCUUAUAGUUGGCUUGACAAAGCAUAAUUCUCUCAUAACAAACUUUCAAAUCAUUACAGUAGCUUAGCUACUUUAGUUGAUGUGACCGAGGAAUCCCUUCUAGAAUCAUAGGUGGCAAGGGAGGGUUUGCUAGCUCUCCAUUUGCACUGGCCAUUGUGAAAAACCAGCUUCUGUAUUCAAAUCUUUCCUUCAUUUUUUUAAAUUUUUUUUUUGGCAGCGCUUGUGCUGGAACUUACUCAUUGUAACUGAAUCCUCAGGGCUUUUCUUGUUUUAGAUCAUGGACUGUGCACGUGACACUUAAAUAAUUUUCUAUGUAUUUAAAGAAAAAUGCACCAGGAUGGUGUCUGUGCACGUGACUAUUAGAGGAGCGUCUGUAGAAGUACCUGGUUUGGUCAGUGCAGUUGUGCAAUCUGAGGGCCUUGUUUCCUCCUCCCCUUUCCCCUUCUCCCCACCAAAGGAAAAUAUCCCUCUUAAUGAUUUCGUAGUUCAGUUUACUGAAUGAUUACCACCUGUAAUUCCUCUUUGGAUUGUGUAGACUCAACAUGAGACAUUCCUUUCUGCUUUCUGGAGGGCACCAGGGGCCUUUCUCUUUGAUAAAUUUUUUUUGUCUGUUGACAAAAACAAAAAUCUUUUUUCAAAUGUAGUGCUGGUGAAAAGGUAGGGCUGAGUGAUUACCUUAGCCACAGGGUGGCUGAGCAGGAACUUUAGAAGAAAAUCCUGAGCUUUCCUGUCCAUUCCCAGCAUCCAGCUCCUAUUCUAGUGCCUCUUCCCUGCAGGGCAGGGACCCCUUGGGAAAUCGAGGAGGUGGGACGGGCUGGGCCCUGUGUCCCAGGUUUCACAGGGCUCAGGGUUAUGCUCCCGCUUGAAUCUGGACGUGAAUCUGGUAAAAAUAUCAAGUACCUGUGGAACUCCCUGAUUCUAUACCCUCUUCCUUCUUUCUGCAAGGCAGAGGAAUAAUAUUUUUAAAGGUUAUUUUGUUUUAGUUUUAAAUAGCAAAACACAAGCUGCAUUUUUAUUUAUUUUGCAUAAGAAAGGUAAAUCUUUUUACAAAAAAAAGUAUAGAGUUGGAAACUCUGGGAAAACUUACGGAAAUACACAAAUGCUUCUCUGUAAUGUGCAAUAUGCUUUGCAACUGUAGAUGAUAUUUUAUGUUUAAUCUGUAAAUAAGAAAUGUAUUUAAAUUAAAAGGGAUCUUUUUGUAAAAGGACCAAAUGUUCUUUUAUAAAUGUAAUAAGGAAUAUCUUGCUCUUUAAAAUUUAUUAGGAUUUUUAUGAGUAAUUUUUAUUAAAAGAUUUCUUUUUUUGA